UGCCCUGGGCUCUUCCUGACAUUUAAUGCCAAGCUCCUUCUCCUGGCUAGUUUGCAUGUUUUCAGCCUGGGAGGUGCCCCCUGCCAGAUUCUGCUCUCCCACCUCUCAGCAGCCGGGGUUGGGGGUGGGUAGAAAGGGGCCUCCAGACUUGGGGAGGGAGAGGCUCAUCCUUCCUCCCCAGCCAGGGACCUUAGUGUGACUCUGCUGGGGGUCGGAUGGGACCGGGACCUCCCCAGGAUUAUGACGGCGCACCACCAGGAUAAAGACCCCCCUCCUUCUCCCUCUAGCUCUGGCACAGGGGAGACGUGGCUGGAGGGACUGCCCAGCCCGGGGCUCCAGCGCCUGAGACUGGUUGCGGGGCAAGGCCCAGGCCUCUCUGCUCCUGGGGUAGCAAGUUGCUUUGAGGGCUGCUGGGACCUAGCUCCUCCUGCCCCACCCUACCCUCUGUGCCAGGACAAAAGGGGGAUGUGUCUCUGCUGACACUUCACAGGUGGGAACCGGUCCUGAUAACCCCUUAAUAACCCACUCCCACCCAUCUCAACCUUGUUUGAAGCAAUUUCUGUUCUUAGCCUGUCAGGACAGUUCUUUCUGGACUUUUCUCAUCUGUGAUGUUGGAGUCCUUCACUUUGUCCUAACACCCCUCUCCAAGCCUGGAGGUGUGCUCCAGGGCCUGAGGAUCAGGGCGCAGGAAUGUUUUUUCCCUUCAGCCCAUCAAGAUUUUACAGACCAACAACCAGGUGUGUGGAGGGCCUCUGCCUUCCCUGGCCUGUGCUGGGUCUGGAGGGGCCGCAGAAACACGGCAGAUGGAGACAGCAGUCACCACUGUGGACACACACCUCUCGGGAGACAGUGAAGCCUUCUCACAUCGCUGUCCUGCCUGGUGACUUCAAAAUCCAGACACACAGCUGUCUUUAUGAGUCCCUGUUUCACUGCUGAAGAGGCUGAGGCCAAGAGGAUCGGCCAAGGGGCCUCAGGCAGGAGCAGCAGAGCUCCGGUGACAUCCGUGUGUUCUCAUGCCCUCAACGACCCUGCUGGGCAGGGCUGUGGGGAGCAAGAGACCCAGGAAACCUCACGACCCCUGUCCUGUGGCAAGCUGGGAGACACAGCCGCCAGCCCAAACAGCAGCGGCAUGGGCAGCGCCAGCCCGGGUCUGAGCAGCGUAUCCCCCAGCCACCUCCUGCUGCCCCCCGACACGGUGUCGCGGACAGGCUUGGAGAAGGCGGCAGCGGGGGCAGUGGGUCUCGAGAGACGGGACUGGAGUCCCAGUCCACCCGCCACGCCCGAGCAGGGCCUGUCCGCCUUCUACCUCUCCUACUUUGACAUGCUGUACCCUGAGGACAGCAGCUGGGCAGCCAAGGCCCCUGGGGCCAGCAGUCGGGAGGAGCCACCUGAGGAGCCUGAGCAGUGCCCGGUCAUUGACAGCCAAGCCCCAGCGGGCAGCCUGGACUUGGUGCCCGGCGGGCUGACCUUGGAGGAGCACUCGCUGGAGCAGGUGCAGUCCAUGGUGGUGGGCGAAGUGCUCAAGGACAUCGAGACGGCCUGCAAGCUGCUCAACAUCACCGCAGAUCCCAUGGACUGGAGCCCCAGCAAUGUGCAGAAGUGGCUCCUGUGGACAGAGCACCAAUACCGGCUGCCCCCCAUGGGCAAGGCCUUCCAGGAGCUGGCGGGCAAGGAGCUGUGCGCCAUGUCGGAGGAGCAGUUCCGCCAGCGCUCGCCCCUGGGUGGGGAUGUGCUGCACGCCCACCUGGACAUCUGGAAGUCAGCGGCCUGGAUGAAAGAGCGGACUUCACCUGGGGCGAUUCACUACUGUGCCUCGACCAGUGAGGAGAGCUGGACCGACAGCGAGGUGGACUCAUCAUGCUCCGGGCAGCCCAUCCACCUGUGGCAGUUCCUCAAGGAGUUGCUACUCAAGCCCCACAGCUAUGGCCGCUUCAUUAGGUGGCUCAACAAGGAGAAGGGCAUCUUCAAAAUUGAGGACUCAGCCCAGGUGGCCCGGCUGUGGGGCAUCCGCAAGAACCGUCCCGCCAUGAACUACGACAAGCUGAGCCGCUCCAUCCGCCAGUAUUACAAGAAGGGCAUCAUCCGGAAGCCAGACAUCUCCCAGCGCCUCGUCUACCAGUUCGUGCACCCCAUCUGAGUGCCUGGCCCAGGGCCUGAAACCCGCCCUCAGGGGCCUCUCUCCUGCCUGCCCUGCCUCAGCCAGGCCCUGAGAUGGGGGAAAACGGGCAGUCUGCUCUGCUGCUCUGACCUUCCAGAGCCCAAGGUCAGGGAGGGGCAACCAACUGCCCCAGGGGGAUAUGGGUCCUCUGGGGCCUUCGGGACCCUGGGGCAGGGGUGCUUCCUCCUCAGGCCCAGCUGCUCCCCUGGAGGACAGAGGGAGACAGGGCUGCUCCCCAACACCUGCCUCUGACCCCAGCAUUUCCAGAGCAGAGCCUACAGAAGGGCAGUGACUCGACAAAGGCCACAGGCAGUCCAGGCCUCUCUCUGCUCCAUCCCCCUGCCUCCCAUUCUGCACCACACCUGGCAUGGUGCAGGGAGACAUCUGCACCCCUGAGUUGGGCAGCCAGGAGUGCCCCCGGGAAUGGAUAAUAAAGAUACUAGAGAACUGA